AAUAAUAAUAAUUAUUAUUUUUAAUGGAUACAGAGUCUUGCUAUGUUGCUCAGGUUUGUCUCAAACCCCUGGCCUCAAGUGAUCCUCCUGUCUAGGCCUCCCAAAAUGCUGAGGUUACAGUUAUGAGCCACGGGCACAUGGCCAGAUUAAAAAAGUAGACUCAAAAAAAAAAAUUUGUAUCGCAUCACCUAGACUUUUCUAUAAUUUUCAUUUCUGAUUCUUUGGGAUGGAACUCAUAAUCUCUCAGGGUGGCACUACUUGCUUUUGAAUCUAUAGUGCCUAUUUUGUUCUGUAAUGGGUUUAAUUUACCCAUUUCAAGUCAAUUGCAUUUUUAUAUUCUAGGAUCUAGAUCCAGAGUGAAUGGGGGAAAUUAUGGUUUUGAUACAUGAACUAUGAACUUAGGACAAAGCUUAAAACUCUUUUGAAAAAAAAUAAUCAAAGUUUUGGGCUUAUAUUGUCUGCAUAAAUUGGAAAAAUGGGGUAAUAAGAAACAACUUUAAUUAGCUAACAUUGAACAGUUUUAAGGAUGGGGAUUAAUGUAGUAUUUCCCUAAGAGUGUUUAUUUUAUUUUAUUUUGAAUUUUUUAUUUUUGUGGGUACAUAGUAGGUAUAUAUAUUUAUGGGUUACAUUAGGUAUUUUGAUGCAGGCAUGCAAUGUGUAAUAAUCACAUCAGGGUAAAUGGGGUGUCCAUCACCUCAAGCAUUUAUCCUUUGUGUUUCCAACAAUCUAAUUGUACUCUUUUAGUUAUUUUUAAAUGUACCCCAAGAGUUUUUAAGAGAAUUGUUCAAAUGAUCACUGCACUUCGUGUAAGCCAUUCUCAGAGGCAGUUUCUGAGAAUGUCAUGGAAACUACGUAAACCAAGCUGAUUCAUUUUUAGAUUCUCCUCACGUUUGUCACCUUUGCUCUCAUUCUUUGAGGUGUUUGGUUUGACUUACGUGGGUAGGCAGUCUAAGACUAGUACUUUGGCCUGAUAAUUUGAUUGUUUGUCACAUGCCUCUUUGUUUUCAAAGCCUUUUCCAAUCCUUAGUCAACCUCUUAACCACUGGGAAUGUUGGAUUGUCUGAAGUUGAAGCACAGUUUUCUCUCUGAGCCCUCUAAAGAAGUCUUUUAGUUGUUGAUAAUCAAAUUUGCUCCUUCAGAAACUAAAAUUCCAAGGUAUUUUAUGAACUUAAGGCAGAUAAGAUGAGGUCUCAGGUAUCAAAAUCACUAAUAAUUAAUUUGCUGCCACUAGCUGCUGCUCCAAAGCUGACAUUUAAGCUAUGUGAAGAGGACCAAGUCUAAACUGGAUUUUAUAACCCAGUCAAAGCUGGGGGUGAUGAAGACUCUCAUUGACUUUAUGUAAUGGAGAUUUAUAUAGGGAUAUUGGAGAGUUGGGGAUACUGCUGAAUAUUUCUAAAUCUCCUCUUUCUUGAAAAACUUAUGCUUUUAUUCCUCAGUGGCUUUUCCUAUUUCCUGUUCAUUAAGUCAACAAAUAUUGAGCCCCAGCUAACACCAUGCAUGAGUGACAAUGUCAAAACCAUAUCCUUCUACUCCCCCACCAAACCAAAUCAGAACCAAAAUUUGUCUUUGGAAAAUGGAUCUCUUUGUCACUAAGGUUCAAAAUUUUGGAAUAAGGUUUGAAUUCAGGGGCGAGUUAUCAGGAUGUGUUUUGUCGUUCCAACCUCCUGUCUCAAGUCAUUCAUGACUGUGCAGCAUCAACCAGUCAGAUAUUUGAGGACCUUCUGUGUUACUUGUCCUGUGCUCCAUGUUGUUGGAAAGCCUACAAAGUAGCUGGGGAGAAAAGGCUAAGACUCAGAUAAUGCUCAACCUCCAUGACUGGGAGGAUCUUGUCAGGCUCUUUUAACUAGUAUUCAGCCCAACACAUUUUCUUAGUAAACAUGAGGAACUUGGCUUAGCAUUCAGAAAUAAUAAGGCCCAUUUUAUUUCCCUUCUCUUUACCUUUUAUAAUGUAAUUCGAGGACCCUUGAAAGGUAACCUCCAGCUUUUUUUCUUCCCAGGCUAUCUUUCGAAAUUUAUUUUUUUAGUUUAAGGCGAGGAUAAAAAGGGCACACCAAAGGGAAUUGGGAAGUUUUAUUAGAAUCUGGAUGGAAUGUCUUCAGGCUCACUGACAGAUUAAUUUGUGCCCUAUUUCCGCUACAAAACAUUCUGACUGCCUGCACCAUUCCACAUGCUUUUGACUGGUAGACUAGUACAGAUGCUCCUCAGCUUGCAGUGGGGUUAUGUCCUGAUAACCACAUUAUAUUGAAAAUAUCUAAGUUUAAAACGCAUUUAAUACACCUCGCCUACUGAACAUCAGAGCUUAGCCUAGCCUACCUUAAAUAUGCUUAGAACACUUACAUUAGCCUGCGGUUGUGCAAAAUCAUCUAACACAAGCCUGUUUUAUAAUAAAGUGUUGACUAUCUCAGGUAAUUUACCAAAUACUGUAUGGAAAGUGAAAAAUAGAAUGGUUGUAUAGGCAUUUGAAGUGUGGUUUUUACUGAAUGCGUAUCACUUUUGUACCAUUGGAAAGUCAAAAUCGUAAGUUGAACCAUUGUAACUGGGGACUGUCCGUGUUCUGUUUUAGAGCUGCACAUGCAUUUCUGCACCUGCCAACAGAAUUUUAUGCUUACUGGGUCAGUAGUUUGUUUUCAAACCUACUUACACUAGUUGUAAUCAUCAUCAUCGCCUAAUUUAAUGUUUUGUGAAUCUAUGAAAUAUAAGUGCAAAAAUUGAAUUGCUUCUAAAUGAGAUGCUUUGGAAAGUUUUAGUAAAGGUAAAAAAUUUUGCUGAAAUAAAACUGCCGUUAAUUAAAUAUACAUAAGAUAAUUGCAAAAAGUUGGAGCAAAAAUUGUAAGAAUCUAAAAAGAGCCUGUAUUCAGAUUGCAUUGAAAACACUUUUAAGUUCUGUCUCCACAUUAAAUAAACAAACUGGAAAUUAUAGAUGAUGCCUGUGGGUUUGUGCUGGAAAGACACCCUUAUUGAUAUUCCUCUGACCUAUUAUGAUGAAAAAGCCUUGGCCUUUUGUCAAAAAAUUGUGAAUGAAUGUAUGUUUAGAUGUUUUAAGGUGAAUUUAAAUGUUUUGGCUAUAACUAGCGUUUUAAAAAUCUCAAUCUUUAAAUGCCUUUUAAGAUAAAAUGUCCAGUUCCUGCUUCUAAUAGUCUUAGCUUAAGGGACUUGUACUUAACAAAACAUUUCCAUAUUCUAACACACGUACCCCCUGGUUUAGGAUCAUUGUGUGUAUGGAAUUAUCCCCACAUGGGGAAACGGGAAAAAAGGCUGAGAAUUACUGGUUUGUCCUGGGUUGAGGUACACAUGUCUCACUUGGCAUUACCUAUAUUUAAUUCCUUUCACACCCUGACGUAACUGGUUAUCAGUUUUUUUGUGUUUGUUUUUUUCCUGAUACUAGCUUUAGAGAUAAAAGGACAUUGGAAAUACUGCCUGUUUAAUCAGUUUCUCUUAUGUUAGUCCAGAAUAAGGGGAAAUAUGAUUUGGGAAGCAAAAUAAGCUCAUUUGGAAAGGCAAAGUUAUUUUAGUGAUCUUUUAAUGUAUUUCUUUAAGGUAUACACACAGUCACACACACACAAACACACACUCACAUACCCCACAUGGGAUAAUGGAUAACUUAAAGAUGUACUCAAUCUGUCCGGGAAGGAGAAAUUCUCUCAUUAUAUGUAGAUAAAAGCUGGGACCACUUAGUUCCUGGAUUUUUGCAUUCAUUCAAGUGACUUGGCUUUUUGGCCCAAGUGGUGCAUUCCAGCUAUCCUUUGCUACUCUUACAUUAGCAAUUCGAUUUAAUUUUUAAUCCCAACCAUGGAAAAAUUAUGUGUUAAAAAAGCAAGUAGAAAGUUGUUUUUCUAUUCCAAUAAAGAGAGUGGGAGGAGAAAACUUAACAAAUUUGAAGUUGAAAUGUGUGAUUUCUUAAACUAGAGUCAUUUCAGAGUUUUUUUGGUCUUUAAAUAUACUUUUGGAAUGUUUUCACUUGCACAUUGGCUUUGCCACUAAACCCGUUGCACACACUGCAGUGGUUUCCUAAUUGAAAUUGUGCAAUUCCACGUAUUUUUCCUGUGAUUACAUUUCAGUGGGUAAAAGUUGAUCUUCACAACAACUUUGUGAGGUGGGUUGGUUGGAUAUUAUUCUUCACCCAACACCUUCACCUCCUUUUUGAUUGAUCAGGACUCAGACUUGCCCAAGGUAAACAGUGAUGAUCUUAAGGCCAAGUCUUCCGACUGUUGUUUACACCUUCUUCUACCAUGUAGAGAUACCACCCUAGGCUGCAGAACACUGUUGUCAGUUUGGAACUUCCAUGAUGAUGGAAAAUGUUCCACUAUUGCAUAGUUGCCAUCACAGUCGUCAAAUAUGGCUUUUAAACACUUGAAAUGUGGCUGGGAUAGCUGUACAACUAAAAUUUUUAUUUUGUUUAAUUUUAAUUAAUUUACACUUAAACAGCCACAUGUGGCAAGUGGCUACCAUACUGUAUAGUGCAGCUUAGGAAUGUAGUCUAGAAGUAUUUAUAGUCUGAUCUUUCUCUUUUUUCCAAGAAAAACUUUAUUUAUUUAUUUAUUUUUUAUUAUACUUUAAGUUCUAGGGUACAUGUGCACAGCAUGCAGGUUUGUUACAUAUGUAUACAUGUGCCAUGUUGGUGUGCUGCACCCAUUAACUUGUCAUUUACAUUAGGUAUAUCUCCUAAUGCUAUCCCUCUCCCCUCCCCCUACCCCACAACAGGCCCCAGUGUGUGAUGUUCCCCUUCCUGUGUCCAAGUGUUCUCAUUGUUCAAUUCCUACCUAUGAGUGAGAACAUGUGGUGUUUGGUUUUUUGUCCUUGUGAUAGUUUGCUGAGAAUGAUGGUUUCCAGCUUCAUCCAUGUCCCUACAAAGGACAUGAACUCAUCCUUUUUUAUGGCUGCAUAGUAUUCCAUGGUGUAUAUGUGCCACAUUAAGAAAAACUUUUUUUAAUUAACAAAAAUUCCAAACAUACACAAGAGUAGAGAAAAUAGUAUAAUGAACCCUUCCGUCCCAUCACCUAGCCCAGUCAUCAAUUCUUGGCCAAUCAUUUUUUUUUUUUUUUUUUUGCAUCUCCCCCUCCCAUUUAAAUUCAUAGCCAAUCUUGUAUUGUCUAUUUACCAUUCUCUUUAGCCUCCUCGCUCCCUUCUCUAACCUCUUCCCUCACCUCUCCCCAAAUUAUUUUGAAGCAAAUAACAGGCACUGUCUGAUCUCAUUUUUGUUUUAAGAGCCAAGCUGUGACCUGGGGAAGGAGGGGCAGUGAAAGGGAUCAAGGAGAGAUACUCGAGGAUCUUCAAACGUAUCUGUGAUUUAAAAAGAAAGGAUGAAGUAUAUGGAUGGUAAAAGUUAUGGUUUAACAAAGAUAGGUCAUGAGUAUUCAGAUACGUGAUACUCUGUAUGCUUGAGCUAUUUCAUCACCAUCAUCAUCAUCAAAAAGCCAAGUUGGAACUCACGUGGAAGUUACUGUGCCAGGCCUCGCUUACCUGUGCUUAUCUUGAACUUUGGGUUUAUGCAUAAUUUAAAACACUUAAACAUUAUUUCUGUGCAAUAUUUAUCAUUGAGCUUUAUUGAAUACCAGCAGUGCUGUAGAGUCAUGGGACCUUUAAAAGGUCAAAAGAAAGCUGAGGAUCAUUUUAGUCUAGUCUCCUCAGAAAGCUUAGCUCCUGAGAGAAGUAGCUUGAUUUGAGCUCAUAUCAAGUGGCCCAGUGCUUCCUGUCAUUUACCACACUUGCCAGAACGACUGAUUCACUGAGUUAAAACUUGGCAUUGCUAAGUCAUUCUUACCUAGCUUUUAAAAUGACAGAUUCUUAUGACCUCUUUGAGAGCAGAGAUAUGCCUAAGUCUGCUUGCUUGGCAUUGUAGAUACUCUUGUUAGAGAGAAAUGUUUUCAUCAUUAAUAGUAUAAAAGAGUCAUUUAUCAGGCCACACAUGGUGGCUCACACCUGUAAUGCCAGCACUUUGGGAGGCCAAGGCAGGCGGAUCACCUGAGGUCAGGAGUUCGAGACCAGCCUGGCCAACAUGGUGAAACCCCAUCUCUACUAAAAAUACAAAAAUUAGCCAGGCGUGGUGGCGUGCACCUGUAGUCCAGGCUACUUGGGAGGCUGAGGAUGGAGAAUCACUUGAACCUCGGAGGCAGAGGCUGCAGUGAGCUGAGAUUGUGCCACUGCACUCCAGCCUGGGCAACAGAGCCAGACUCCAUUUCAAAAAAAAAAAAAAAAGGAGUCAUUUAUCAAAUUUUGUCUUUUGGGCUUAGAAUUUAUGCCUAUUACUGGUGGUAUAAUAUUAUGUAUUAUUGCCUAUAUAAUACAUAUUAUAUAUAAUUUAUUAUAGGAAAUACUUAUUUUAAUAUUUCUAUUUCUAAAAGAAACUUGUGUAUCAAGUACAUUUUAGUCAUAUGAACAGACACAUUGAAGGAAAUAAUGCUUGCACCAAUGAUAUUUAAAAGUGCAGUUUUCCUCACAACAUAAAGCAAGAAUUGUUGCUAUGCUUUUAUAGUUUAAUUUAGGAGCCAAUAGUGAUUUUCUCUCAUGACAGAGUGCAGAAUAUGUAUAUUCUAAAUUUGGAACCCUAUACACGGUAUCUUAGGAUUUAAAGGGAAUGGUUUUGUGAUGGUAAAAGGAUCUUGUAUCAUCGGAAAUGCUCUCAGGGCUUGGCUCAGCUGUCUAUUGAUGUAAAAAGAUAAUGUGCUUUAGAAAAAGAGCUAUAUUGAAAUUUUCACCAACUUUCUGAUGGACAACUGCAAGCUUUCAGCUAUAAGAGGCUGCCAUUUCUUUUACAUGGUUUUGUCUCCAGCAGAGUCUGCCCUUUGUGUUCCCUUAGGCUUUGUUAACUAUGUUCCUGGGAGAGAAGGAAAGUCUGUGUUUCAUCUCAUCAUCUGUGUUGCAGUUUAGUCCAGUUUGCUUUAUUCCAUGGUGAGUGGAGAGAGUAAGUAGUUGGAUGGCGCCCUACAUUUUAAUGUUACCACAACUCAAGAUUUAUGCUAGUUUUGCAAAGAAUUCUCUCAUGAAAUGAGUUUUAUCUCCACUUGACAAGAGACAGUUGAAUCCACAGUAGGGCUAAGAAGAAGAUUUAGGAAGAUAUUUGGUCAAAUUAGUUAUCCUGUGCUUUUUAUGCAGGAUAGAGACAGGAAACUGUUAAGGCUUGUAAAAUGACUAUGACCUGAUUAGGCAAAUAUAGCAACUAUUUUCAGCAAAGAAGCCACAAGAUGAGUAUAGCUGACUUUUUUUUUUUUUAAUGUAUAAAGUUUGGAGAUUUUCCAGUGAUUUUCUAAUAGACCAAAUUUAAAUCUAACAAUAAUACAUCUUGAAAAAAAUUAAAAAUUUAUGUAAUCAGCCAGGCAUGGUGGCUCACACCUGUAAUUCCCAGCACUUUGGGAGGCCGAGGAAGAUAGAUCACUUGAGCCCAGGAGGUUGAGACCAGCCCCGGCAACAUGGUGAAACCCCAUUUCUCAGAAAAAAUACAAGAAUUAGCUGGGAGGUGGUGGCGCUCACCUGUUGUCCCAGCUACUCCGGUGGCUGAGGUGGGAGGAUCGCUUGAGUCUGGGAGUUUCAGGCUGCAGUGAGCCGAGAUUGUGCCACUGUACUCCAGCCUGGGAGACAGAGGGAGCCCCUGUCUCAAAAAAUAUUAAGUAGUCUAGAUCUCAGUUAAUGCUUAUGCUUUAUUGUAGUUAGAAAAGUGCUUAACCUGGCCUGUAAUCCCAGCACUUUGGGAGGCCGAGGUGGGCAGAUCACUUGAGGUCGGGAUUUUGAGACCAGCCUGGCCAACAUGGCAAAACCGUGUCUCUACUAAAAAUACAAAAAUUAGCCAGGUGUGGUGGCUCACACCUGUAAUCCCAGCUACUUGGGAGGCUGAGGCACGAGAAUUGCUUGAGUCCAGGAGGCAGAGGUUUCAGUGAGCCAAGAUCAUGCCCCUUUACUGCAGCCUGGGUGACAGAGUGAGACUCCAUCACAAAAAAGAAAAGAAAAAGUGCUUAACCUGAUGUAGCUAUAACAUUAAUAAGAAAUAGAAAUUUAUCUAACUUUCUCUUUAGUUAAUGGCCAAUGGUUUAUACACAGUUUUGGUUAAGCUUCAAUUAGGUUCCGUGUUGAAUUAUUGAUGGCAUGGUAAGAUGAUAGUAAGGGAGGCAAAUGUGUAAGCCAUCUAUGAAUGAGCUUCAUUAUUUAGCUUAUUUAUUUGAGGGAGAAAAAGUACCAAAAAGGCAACCCACAUUCUUCAGUUAAACUGCUGGAAAAACACAUGCCACCUCUUGGCUCUGACUAGGAAAUGGGGGCCUGAUGGUGCCAUAGUCUUCAGUUUUUCAAAAGAAGAGAUGGACAUUUGGAAUUUGAUGUGAAAUUUCCACAUCUGACAAUGUUGGCAACUAAAUGUUUUAAAAAUACUGUGUGGGUCACAUAAACACAUUUGCUGGUUGAGUCUGCCAAUUUGCAAUCUGAUUUCCAUUGGAAAUAAAUUUAUUUGUUUUUCUUGUAUUUGAAUAAAGGAACCAUUAAUAGUUUUUUUUUUUUUGGUAUGCCUUUUAGAAUGAUUUAACAUUUGAACAAUUUAAGCUUUUUGUGUGUGCAGAAAAUGUGGCUGCUUUUAAAAUACAAGUGAAGCAAGUGCUUGAACUCUGAUAUUAAAACAUAUAGAUUGGUUGAGGACAACAUCAACAUUUUUGAAUUGUUUCUGUAACAGGAUUUCUCCAAUACAGGCCCGGCCAUAAGAGAGCAAAUUUGGAGAACCAAAAGUUGAUGUAUGGUGUGAGCAGGCCCACAGCUGAGGGAGUGGGAGGAAUUCUAGAGUGUGUGGUAGCCAAGCAAAUGUGGCUCCGCAAAAACAUAUGCUAUAUAUAGUGAAUGGGGUUGGAUUUUCUAUUUUUGGUUGAGUUCCAAUGACAGUUAAUGGCUGUUCCUAUAGGCCAUGAAAUUAUUUAUGAAUUCGGCAGUGGGACGAUAUAAAAUGCAAGUUGAUAUAGGUAGAAUAAAAUUUGUUACCAAAUUUCAACAAAUUAUUAGUGCUAGAGCCAGAAGGGCCUUCAAAGGUCACCUUAUAAAGGACCUUCCUUUAAGAUGAGGAAACUGAGGCCUGGGGAAUUGAGGCUUAAAUUUCCCAUUAAUCCUUAUUGAGGCCUAAGGACUUAAGUUGAGGCUUAAAUUUCCUGUUAAUCCUUCCCUCUACAGCUGAAACCCAGCAUCCUCCCUUCUUUUCGGUCUUCCUGCCUAUACAAAAAUGCAUCUUCUACGAACUAUUAGUGACAAUUAGAGUCUCAGAAAAACAAAAAAGGCAGAUGUUUUGUAAGCAGACUAUUUAGAAAACAUCUUUCUAAAAGGUUGAUUUAGGCUGUCUUUCUAAUUAUUGGAACAUUUUUAUUGAUAAAAUUUCUGUUGUUUUUGUUAUGAGUUUUGAGACUCUUCUUUUCCGAAGCCUACUCUUUCAUAACCUUUUUAAGAAGCAAAAAGCCAGUGAGAUCAUUAACAGUAAAAGAAAAAGAUGUGGCAAAAUUGCUCUUGAUUUUACAGAAUGUCCUAGUAGUGGGUUGAACCACAUGAAAGUUGAUAUCCAGCCAUUUCUCAACUACAAAAAUAGUAGCUUCAUGUGAUUCAAGAUGGUAGCUUGAGCAAAAUGGUAAUAAGGAGUAUUGAUGUAUCUUCCUAUUCUUAAAGAAAUCCGUGGCAUUUUACAUGGUCAUUGAACACUCCACCCCUCUCAAUUUAUUCUACUCAAACACUGUUACGCCAGAGCAUUUUUAUUGAGAAAUAUGGAGUUGGAAGUUAAAGGUUCCAUGUGUACAUGUGGAAUAGUCUUCUUCCCACAUGUUAUGUUUGGCUUGAAACAUAGUCUUCUUGCCUUGAAGAAAAGACUCCCUAGCUAAAGUCAGAUGCUGGAUUUGUCUCUAAUUUUUCAGGCCAACAGAAGCAAGUUGGCGGCGGGAGCUCUUUUCAUGCUCAGUCUUGGUCAUGAGCACAAUAGUUUCAUAUGUAGUUCUUAAUAUUACAACUUGCAUUGAGGAUCUGGGACUCUUGAACACAUUGUCUUGUUGUAAUCGUAUCCUAAUUCUGAUUUGGGAGACAGGGUGAAUGAGCCUCCAGAGACCAGUAUUGAACUUUAGACCUCUUCUUCUGCUGGUUUUCUAAAUCGAAUCCACUGAAUAUUUGUUUGGCCAAACAAAUUUUUAAAAUAAGUGGCAUUUUAGCAUUUUGGAGAUUACAAAAGGUACAAAAUAUGAGACAUUUGAACUUCACUUUGAAAGUUACAGAGAAAUUUGAGAAAAUGUUGGGAACUCUGAAUCAUAUUUCAGGCCCCUAACUAAAUAAAAUAAAUCUUUGACUUUGGGCAUCAAGGGAAUUAAUAAAUGUAUCCAUGCGAAUUUUUCUUAAGAAAUUAGAAAAGAGAAGUCCAUAUGCAAUCCAGUCGAUAGGAGUAGGGUAAACUCUACCGACUUCAUGGUUCAUAAAGAUUAGAGUGUAUCACAGCUGAGUAAACACAACCAAGGAGGCAUCACAAACAGCAACAUAGUAAUGGGAUUUUUCUCUACUACUUUAAACCAGAGGGUUAGUUAAAAAUUCACUUCUGACAUUUCUAGCCCUUUUCUGACUAUUAGUUAAAAAUUCAGAUGCUUUCCUCCAGUUCUUAAAAAGCAUUUCAUAAUACUUUUGUAUGAACUGUAGAACUAAAGGGCCCUUUUCUUGGGGUUUCCAAAAGAAAAAAGGUAUUGGAGAGACUAAAUCUAUUUUUUCUCUCUUAUUUCUGCAAAAAUGCCCUUCCAUACUUCUGUUCCCUUCAGAAUAAAUAACAGCUCAACUCCCAGCAUGACAUGCAUGCCCUUCCGAGACUUCAUGCCUGUCUUCCUACAAUCUCCAUUAGGCUACCUGCUGGGCCCUGUGUGUGUACCCUUCGCUUACCUCUGCUUUUGCAUUUCACCUAAAUGCCUUUCUCUUUGGCCUGUUUCCAGUCUCUCUAUCUAGUCAUCCUUCAGGACUCUCAACCAGGCAGAGUUAGGAGGACUAGUUUUCUGAAUUCCCAUUUUUCUUAGGCUUCUCUAAUCAGCAGAUACUGUGUUGUACCAUAAUAGUUUUCACGCCUUAUUAAUUUUUGUAUCUUAAACACAGCAUAGAGUAGUGGCUAGCACAAAGGAGUUAUUCAGUAAAUGCUUCAAAAGUAAUUGUGCAGUUACAGGCUCAGGUCUCUUGCUAUGUAGAGCGACUUAGUCAGAAAACAUUACUGUGGCAAAACAUCCUAAAAGGAGAUUGCAGAACAAAGAAUUUAACGAUCUCCUAAAUUUUCUCCAGGAAUUCUUACAGUUAUCAGUAUUUAGUGGUUGAGCAUCUGACAACAGGAAGCUUUGAAGGGCUGAGAAAUAAAGACAUGCAAUGAAUUGGCUUAAGAUUUUAAUUUUCAUUUCACCUGUUUUCUAGUCUCAGUCCAAUUUUUCUCAGCCCUGGAUUGCUCAGACCAUACUAGUUGGAUUGGACAGAGUGUAAUAUAAUUUACUCCUAUCAAUCAGAAAAUACUACAGUGACUGGUGAGGCAGCCUUAGCAAAUGAUAUAGGUAUUUCUCUUUGAUGCUGUAUUCAGGGCCUUCCCCUGGGCUUUUCUUAGUAAUUGAAAUUAUGUGUAUAGGAUUGACUCCUGAAGCUGUUUUUUAUGGAAAUUAGUGGGCAUCUUUCAGUAUUUUCAUUUUCAUUGCUUAUUUGCUUCCAGAAAACUACCAACAUGCUUGAUGAAAGUUCUAGAAAUAAUGUGAGAGGUGAUUAUUCAUUAGAUAUCUUUGUCCUGUGGAAGUGGGGAAACAGGAUUCAUUGGAACAAUAAGUAUUUACAUUUUAAAAGUUUAUAUAUGAUAUCUGUAUGUAUAUCUUACAUAAACAUACAUAAAUGUCUAGCAGAAUUGAUGUUGAAUUAAUAGAGAACAACAUUUUAAAUAUUUUCUACUGUGGAAUUGUUUAAUGUGGGAAAGACUAUACAAGGUGCUUCAUAGUUUCAAUAUAGUUCCAAUCAGUUGAAACCAUUAAAAACCUAUGAUACAUUAAUAUAUCAAACCUAUGAGAUGUUAAUAUUAUAUGCAUUUUACAAGUAAAGAUAGAGGCUCAGAAGUAACUUUCCCCAAAGUCAUUCCCCUAAAAUAUGGCAGAGCUGGAGUCUUUACUUCUGACUCCCAGCCAAUGUUUAUCCCACUAUUCCAUGCUGCUUUUUUUUAUAUUAAUUAUGGAGAGGUUUUUUUUUUUAGCCUUUCACCUAAAAUAUUGAGAUUUGAGUACUAAAUUUAAGAAUAGCACAUGGACUUCAUGCAGACAUCAAUGUAUACUGGUGAAAGGAAACACUAAUUUUUAGCUUAAGAUUAGAUUUAGAUUUAGAUUUAGAUUAAGAUUAGAUUUAAGAUUUAAAUCUUUCUACGUAUUGUGAUCAGAAUAUUGAGGAGGUUGUUUUAGCUAAGUACUUUUUAAUUGUGACCUUUGAAUCUUGUCUUAAGCACAACACUUACGAAGAUGCCAAGACUUUAUGAGCUUCUUAGAAGGGCAGUAUUCACUUGAGAAAGCAGGAAAAAGGAAACCACUUUAAAAUAAAAAAACUUUGGAGCUAUUCAUUGAUACACUGUUCAUCUUUAAAGAACGUGGUGAAGGUCUAGGUAUAAAAUGCCAAAUGGUUGUCACAGCUGCCCCAUACAGCUCUGCAUUGUCUUCUUAAAAACAGACCUUUUAAAAUAUGAGGAUGUAAGCUAUUUUUUUAAAAGUAAUUGUUAACUAAAGAUGGCCGGUGGAUCCACAAGAUACCACAAGCUCCAGGUUGUUACGAUCCCCAACUACCAUGACUUAGUGAGGUUGGACAUCUUUUUAUGUGGUUAUUGGCCAUUUCUAUUUAUUUCUCUGCAAAUAACGUAUUCACAUCCUUACCUUCCUCCACUACCUGCCCCCCUACUGCCCUGCCAAUUGGGCUAUUUAUCUUGUUGAGGUUCAUCCUUUAUUGUAUGUGCAAAUAUCUUCUCCUAGCCAGUCAUGUAUCUGUACUUUUGUUUUUGGUGUCUUGUUACACAGAAGUUCUAACUGUGCCAUCUUUUCUCUUUGGUUUGUACUUUUGGUGUGUUGUUUUAGAAAUCUAGAUCACUCUUCACUGAAAUUCACUUAAUUAUAUUUAACUACUGUUUUGUCUUUUGCUUGGUGGUUUAGAAGGGGCAAGAACAUAGCAACUGCUAAGAAACACAGUUCAUUCACCCAGUGGGAGAAGUACUGAACUAAUAAAUUAGAAGCAACUCAAAGAAAGCAAACAGCUUGGAACCUAAGGCAUGAAAAGGAAGAGCACUCAGGAAUCCAGCCUUUUUAGUUGGGGCAGGCAAUUAAUGCUCUGUGAUUUGAAGAAAUGUUUAUGAGGUAAUUAACACCUAACUUGUAAUUAGCAGUUGAGUACAAACUGAGCUAGAUGAAAAACAAGCAAGGGAGCCCUUAAGUUAGUGAUAGGGUCGUUAACUAAGGUUGUUAAUGUUUGCUGUUUUGGGGGAGAUAUCCCAUUUUAGUACUCCUUUCACUUAGGUUAUUUUCUGAUUUAUAGAUUAAAAUUCUCAUCAAAACAAUAAUAAGUAAUAAUACUGGGCACUCAUUCUGCUAGGCACUGUGUCUAAGGACUUCAUAUACAUGAUCUCAUUCUGUCAACAGACUUAUGAGUAGAUGCCAUAAUUAUGCCAUUUUACAGAUGAGAAAACAGGCUCAGAAAGGCUAAUUAACACUCCCAAAGUCCACAGCUGGCAAGUAAAUGGUGCCAGGAUUGAAGUCAAUUCUUUCUUCUCUCACAGGUGCCCAAAUGUGAUGUUACACAUUUUUAAAAAUAAAAAGUAGAUGAGAAGAAACCGGGUGGUGAGUAGUUGAAGUCAGUGAUGGGGCCUGUUAUGCUUUAAAUCAAGUAUCGUUGGCAUGCCCUGGGAGAGUUAGUUGCUCUUAAAGUUUCUGCAGGACUUUAUCACUCAAAGCCUGUGUGGGGGGAAACAAAAAAGUCAAAGCUCCAUCUCUCCUGGGGUCCCUGCUUUUCUACAUUCGCUUUGCUGCUACCCACCAGGAUGACAGACGGGUCUGCCUCUCUUUUCCAGCCCCAGCCUUGUUCCACAGCAUCCCUUCAGUCAGUCAGGUCCAGAGAAACCCACCUGUCACUCUGGUGCAAGGGAACUGGCUGUGGCUUGCAGUGCGUGUGUGCAUGAUACAGCAUACGUGUGUGUGGAGCAGCCACGCAGCGCAGCACAAGGGAGGCAGCUCAGCUGUUGAUGCCCAGAGGAGGGCCCUCUCCCAAGGUUCCUCAUCAGCUCUUCAGCUCUCCACACAGCUCAGCAUGGAUUUCCUCAGACCAUCCCAAACAUAACCUUACAUUUUGGUGAAAAUUUGUCUACUACUUUUUGUAUGACACAAAUCGAGCAAACAGCACAGAAACCAAAAUCUAUUUAUUUGGAAAUAUUCUGAAGCGAUUCACUGGUAUAAUUUCAUAGUGUUAAAGCGGGUUAGAACCCAGGCUCUGUUACUUACUUGCUCUAAGAACUUGGGCGAAUUUCUUUGUGUCUCUGUGACUUUGUUUCCACAUCUGCGAGGAUGUACACUUUAAUGCAUUUUUUAUGCACCUUAGACCAGUGCCUGGCAUAUAAAUAAUACCUUCUGAAUGUUAGCUAGUUUUAGAGAUGUAAAGCACUAAGCCACUAUUUCCAGAGCGGUGGUCCUGGCACUAUUUCAAUACACCACCAACAUUUUAUAUUCGUAUCACUAAUAGUUUUGGUGAUUUGAUACCACUUUUACCUCUCCUCAUAAAUCAAGGCAUUUUGUGGUCUCUAGAGAAGUAGGGUUCAUUUGAGCCCCAGAAUACAGCUUCUGGCUUUGGAUCUAUGCUUUUCCAGCAAUCUUUUGAUCACUCACAUGUUGUCCCCUCAUUUGAGCCUAAAGAAUUGGUUUCUCUCCCCUCUCAUAUUGGUGGUGUUCAUAAGUUCUACCCACUAGCAGUUGAAAUUGGGACAAAAACAUCCCAGAUGUCCCGUGACUCUUCCUAAUUCCUUUUCCUGUUGUCCUCUUUCUUUCUUAAAAUUAUCCCCCUUUGCCAUGGUACUGGUCCACUAUUUAAAGGUCAGUGACUCAUGUUGUGCCUCAACACUCUGCCAAUCCCUGUACCGGAUGCUGGGGAGGCAAAGUGAAUACCACUUCAGGUUUUUGUUACUGGAGAUUUCAUAGAGUGUUAGAGCAGGAAGGGCUCACAAAGAAACAAUCUCAUCUAGCCCUUUUAUUUUACAGAGAAAGAAGCCAAGACCCAGGAGAGUGAGUGACCUGCUUAAGACCCAUAGGCUCAGAACUGGAGCCAAAUCCCCUGACACUUGCCCACACUACAAACCCAAGGACAGUAGAACUAAGGCGUUCUAGAUAGGUCAUUUGUAGACAGAUUCUUCAGUCGUUUCACACUGCCAAGUGGAGAAAACCCAAACUCCCCUUCUAGUCACCGAUCUUGUGUUUAGGACCCUGGACACUGGUUUAUUUAUGGUGAAAAGAAUCUCACUGUUGGAGCUGGGCUGCAGAUGGAAUGAAUCAAGUUUAACUUAGGUCCUCAAUGCAGUUGGAUAUUUUAUGAAUGAAGAGCUUCGAAACUUGUCUUUGUCUGGCCAUGUGGGAUUUGACAGCCUCCCUGACCAGCUGGUCAACAAGUCUACUUCUCAAGGAUUCUGUUUCAACAUCCUUUGUGUUGGUGAGACAGGCAUUGGCAAAUCCACGUUAAUGGACACUUUGUUCAACACCAAAUUUGAAAGUGACCCAGCUACUCACAAUGAACCAGGUGUUCGGUUAAAAGCCAGAAGUUAUGAGCUUCAGGAAAGCAAUGUACGGCUGAAGUUAACCAUUGUUGACACCGUGGGAUUUGGAGACCAGAUAAAUAAAGAUGACAGCUAUAAGCCGAUAGUAGAAUAUAUUGAUGCCCAGUUCGAGGCCUACCUGCAAGAGGAAUUGAAGAUUAAACGUUCUCUCUUCAACUACCAUGACACGAGGAUCCAUGCCUGCCUCUACUUUAUUGCCCCUACUGGACAUUCACUAAAGUCCCUGGAUCUGGUCACCAUGAAAAAGCUGGACAGUAAGGUGAACAUCAUUCCAAUAAUUGCAAAAGCUGACACCAUUGCCAAGAAUGAACUGCACAAAUUCAAGAGUAAGAUCAUGAGUGAACUGGUCAGCAAUGGGGUCCAGAUAUAUCAGUUUCCCACUGAUGAAGAAACGGUGGCAGAGAUUAACGCAACAAUGAGUGUCCAUCUCCCAUUUGCAGUGGUUGGCAGCACCGAAGAGGUGAAGAUUGGCAACAAGAUGGCAAAGGCCAGGCAGUACCCCUGGGGUGUGGUGCAGGUUGAGAAUGAAAAUCAUUGCGAUUUUGUGAAACUUCGAGAGAUGCUGAUCCGCGUGAACAUGGAGGACUUGCGAGAGCAGACUCACACCCGCCACUAUGAAUUGUACCGACGCUGUAAGCUUGAAGAGAUGGGGUUCAAGGACACUGACCCUGACAGCAAACCCUUCAGUCUUCAGGAGACAUAUGAAGCAAAAAGGAAUGAAUUCCUGGGAGAACUGCAGAAGAAAGAAGAAGAAAUGAGACAAAUGUUUGUUAUGAGAGUGAAGGAGAAAGAAGCUGAACUUAAGGAGGCAGAGAAAGAGCUUCACGAGAAGUUUGACCUUCUAAAGCGGACACACCAAGAAGAAAAGAAGAAAGUGGAAGACAAGAAGAAGGAGCUUGAGGAGGAGGUGAACAACUUCCAGAAGAAGAAAGCAGCGGCUCAGUUACUACAGUCCCAGGCCCAGCAAUCUGGGGCCCAGCAAACCAAGAAAGACAAGGAUAAGAAAAAUGCAAGCUUCACAUAAAGCCUGGCAAGCCAAGGAUGUUCCCGCAUUCACCUGCUUUUGCAGUAAUAUCGUAUCUCUGCCAUGUGUGUUCUUUAGUUUUAUUUUAUUUUAUUUUAUUUUUUUACCCUUCCUCAAACACCAGUAACUAUUAUUAACUCGUUUUGCUGAAUGUUGUUGGGUGGUAGAAAAUGAUAGAACAAGGGAAUAACCGCGAAUGCUCUGUGCAGCUGGACUCUGUUUCCGGAAAGUAAAUGAUUUGCUUUUUAUGCCUGUUCUGAAUGGCAGCACGAAGCAGGCCUGUUACUUGUAUGUCGCUUUGGACAGAGGAAAGUGGGGUAAAAUGCUACCUGUACGUCUGACAUGAAAACUUCUCACCGCCUCAGCAGCUGAACUAAAAACCUGAAUAGCCAUGACAAGAGUUUGCAUUUUCUUGAUGAUUCAUCUCCAUGAGUGCACAAUCCCUGAACUCACUGUCUUUUCUCCACACUUGUCCUAAGCCAAGGUAGAUUUGUACGUAGACAGACUGGUGAGCAAGCAUUAUAUUUUAUUUUUACCCUUGCAUGACAUUUUCAUUUUAAUCAAUAACAUUAUUUGGCCUGAGCUUGUGGGUCUGUUCAGACUGUCUCCUCUCAUGGUUUGAAACUGCAUCUGAAUGCCUGCCUUCAAUCCUGGCCAAGUUGGAGUAGACUGGUAUGAGAAAACUAUGAUUAGUUCACAUUUACUGGUGCAUCCUUGAUCCUCUCACAGAUAGAGGUCUUAAAGGUUGGAUCAUGUAACAUUGCUUAGUAGAAGAAUCUUCUUCUAAGGAUGAUGGGCUUUCUACAGCCUGCUUACCACUAACAGUAAGGAAUCUUUCAUAAACACACCUCAGUUUGUUCCCAGUGGGCUUAGAGGGAGGACCUGAUGACUGAUUCCAGGAUACUUGUACUUCUAAUAACAUUUUUCAUGAAUCAUGAGAAAAUUUCCACAGAUACUUCCCUUAGAAAAUUUGCUAUAAACUCUGUAUCAUUGGUAGCACAAAUUUGAGCGAGGCCUUGUCAAUUUUAAGGUGGAAAUAGGAAGGACCACAACAUGACCCGUAAGUCAAGAAGGUAGACAUUUCAUAUCCAGCUUCCUUGCUUAGUCUCCUUUCAGUAUUUGGCAAUAAAAGAAAGAAGAAAUAGAACAGCUGAAGUCUCAAAUCAUUGUCUGGAAUUUUCCUCACCUUGGCUAGCUCCACCUGCUCUUUGUCUAAGGCCCUUGCCUCAUCAGGGAUUAGAACUGGCCCAUAUGCCAGAACCUGUACUAAAUGCCUAAUUUGUAUGGAAGAGUGCAUAUUUAAUCUCUUUUCUAUACUGCUCCUUUCUGAUGCUUAUCCUUUCAUCUGUGUGAUUGUUUUUUCCCCUCUACUAACAAGAUCCUCCCAGCUUUCUCUCUACAUGUAGAAAGGAUAACAUUUCUCAUGAACCCACUGCCCCUCUGCAUUUUCCUCACUGGUUAGAGAUUAAGUAAAUAGGAUAGAAUAUGCUGCGUCUCCCCUGACACACACUUUCUUUUUUGAAUGAGCAAGUCUCCAUUUUGAUUUCAGCAAAGAUUUUUUCUCCUUUUCUUUGUCCUCAACCAUACUUAGAGGAAAGAAGGAAUGGUCUUCCAUGAACUGAUUAUGCUUAAUUAAGCAAAGUAAGGAAAUUAGUUUCAUGGAAGCCUAAACAAAGCUGGAAUAGAAACUACACACUAGACACAGCAGUAGUCAUAGUCUUCACAGGUUUAGGAGCUACUGGACCAACAUUCUUGUUUUUGCUUUUGUUUUUUUAAAUAAUUCUAGUCUGGAGCUAACUGUGGAGCAGCCAAAUAGUAGCUGGCAUGUUGAUUCAAACCAUGGGCUGAAUUUGCUCAUAGGCUGUGCAUCAGACAAAAGCUUGAAUAUUUGUGUUGUAUGCUUGUUCCAACCACCGCUUGUGUGAGCAUUUUUGUGGCUUGUACAGAAAGUACACUUUUAAAUUGUCUCUUGCAUCACUAAAAUUUUUUUAAAAUGAGCAUAACAACGAAAGGCAUCCAGCUGACUUUUUGAUUCCAAGAUUAUUGAUUGGAUUGACUUUUUUGCAUUAAAUUUUUCCCAGCAAAAUAAAUCAUAUGGCGAGUCAGGGAAUAAAAAGUCAAAAGAAACAAAUAGAAGCUUUUUUUUUUAAAAAAUGUAUUGCUUCUGAACUUUUUUCUGCCACUGCUCCCUAGCCCUGUUUAGUUUGUUAUUGCUGCUUUUCUUUUUUCUUUCUGUAUCUAUGCCUUUUUUUCACAGUAGUCCUUGGCUCUGCACGGAAUAAAUGAUACCCUCAAAUCUAAUUGGAUGUGCUUUCGCCUUUGCAUGUAAGUACGGUAGUAAGAAACCUUUGAGAUCUUUCUGACUUUUCAAAAUUAGAGAAAGCAAAUGGGAUGGAUAGAUUUUUUUUUUCUUUUCAAGGGGGGCAGGAAGGUAAUGGUUUGAGUAGCCUUUGUUUAAAAAAAAGACUAAAUAUAUUUAAAAGGCCACAUUUAUAUUUUUUUCACAAGAACCACAUAAUAAAUUCCACUUCUUGACCUGAAUUUGGAAAUCCGAAAUUACUAAUCCAGGCCAGGUGUGGUGGCUCAUGCCUGUAAUCCCAGCACUUUGAGAGGCCGAGGUGGGCAGAUCACUUGAGGCCUGGAGUUCAAGACCACCUUGGCGAACACGGUGAAACCCCGUCUCUACAAAAAAUACAAAAAUUAGCCAGGCGUGGUGGCACGUGCCUGUAGUCCCAGCUACUUGGGAGGCUAAGUCAGGAGAAUUGCUUGAACUUGGGAGAUGGAGGUUGCAGUGAGCCAAGAUUGCACCACUGCAUUCCAACCUGGGUGAUGAAGUGAGACUCUCCAAAAAAAAAAAAGAAAUUAUUAAUCCCUGCCUGUGCUCUACAUAGCCUCAUGGGCAUCAUUGGAUAGCUCAGAGGGCCCUUGAUUCUGGCAAGGCAAAUAAAGCCAGAAUGAGAAAUUACCAUCUUCUACUAGAGAAAACCAAGAGAAAAAUUUUUAUGCUAGGAUGCCUUUAUGACCACUUAAUUUUUUAAUCUUAGUUUAAUGGUCUCUCCCUGGUGCUAACUGCUGACAGUGGCCACCUCUUUUUUGGGGAUUGAGGGGCCUACAUAACUAGCUGGCCUUACCCCAUAUCUUUUGUUCAAACAUAAUACCAUCUUUUUGCUUCUUCUGAACUUUAGAUCUCCAUAACACAUGUACUGUAGAAUGUGAUGGAAAAGCAUUGAUGAGAAUUUAUUGGCAGUUCAGAUUGUGUUUUCCCAACUUAGGCUCUUUAUUAAUUGGUUAAGGUUUUCUCCAAAAAGGGCAUUUCAACAAUGGGAAUUAUUUAAUGUAACAGUGGGCACAGAUUACUUAUCUUCCUUCUCUGCUUUGUGACUCACCAGCAGUAACACACACAAUCCACAUCUUGUGCACCUCAAAUGAACAGACUUGGUUUCCUUGCUUUCUUGACAUUUCCAUGACUGUUUCACAUACAAACUAUUGGGUGAGGUUUUUCAGCUGUUACCGACCCACGUCCUGCUGUCUCUGUGUGGUCCUACAAAAACUGUCCAUUCCCACCCCUUUGCUUUGCCAUUUGCAAGAGUCUGGAAUUGUCAGGUCUCAGCUUCGAAAAGUCCUGGUUCCACUGACAGGACACAUUCUUUAGUGGGAAUUAAGACCUACAAAGUCUAGUUUGUAUGUAGGUAUGAAGGGAAUUUUUUAAAUAAAUUGAAAAGCUGUGAACAGCAUUAGAACUUUGUCUAUUUCUUAAUUUUAAAAUAUGCUGAUAUGCCUUAAACUGUAGUUGUAGAUCCUUGUCAUUUUGCUGUUUGAAAAUAACCAAUGUGUUUUCUAAAACUGUCGUGUAAUCUACUUUCAUUGUUAAUGCAGAAUUGUCAUAUAUGUAAGCUGCAUGUUAGACAUUUGUCUUUUUUAAACUAAAGUAAUUGUAUUGAUGUGAAGCAUAUCAUUUUUUCAAAUAUGAAAGUGAUCACUUAGCAACAUGCUUGGUAAUUUGGCAUCUGUUAAGGUAGGAGAGUGGUGAACAGAUAAUCUAUGCAUAUAUCACUAGUGCCAAGACAUAAAGCGGGGGAAAAUAUAUUUUUACCCAAACAUUA